AGAGCGCUGGAGCGCUGGAGCUCUGGGCUGUCCCGGGCUCAGUCUCGCCGGCGGCCCCCGCUCCCGGAUCCCCAGCGCCCUGGCCAAGAAGCUUCCUCGGCUCCCCCUCUUCCCUCUCCCUGACACGGUUGUGCAGAGGGCGCGGUGGCUCAGGUGACACGGGCAUCCUUCAAGGAAGGGCGGCGGGACGGCGGGGCGCUGGCGCUGUCGUUGGAGCUGGAGGAGGACGGGGACCCUCCAUUCUCCGCUGCCCUAGCGCCCAUCCCGCGCCGGGAGCCUGGGACCCUAACUUGGAUGGCGAGUAACCCAUGGGCCAGGUAGCGUUCUAUGCCAACCUUGAAUGCCAUCAGGAAGUCACUGGACAGCAAACUCUUCCAAGAUCAUAACUUGGCUGUUGGAGCAACCUGGAAAAGAAGAAAAAAGAAAAACCAUGGCAAAAGUAAAUAGAGCUCGGUCUACCUCCCCUCCAGAUGGAGGCUGGGGCUGGAUGAUUGUGGCUGGCUGUUUCCUUGUUACCAUCUGCACACGGGCAGUCACAAGAUGUAUCUCAAUUUUUUUUGUGGAGUUCCAGACAUACUUCACUCAGGAUUACGCACAAACGGCAUGGAUCCAUUCCAUUGUAGAUUGUGUGACCAUGCUCUGUGCUCCACUUGGGAGUGUUGUCAGUAACCAUUUAUCCUGUCAAGUGGGAAUCAUGCUGGGUGGCUUGCUUGCAUCUACUGGACUCAUCCUGAGCUCAUUUGCCACGAGUCUGAAGCAUCUCUACCUCACUCUGGGAGUUCUUACAGGUCUUGGAUUUGCACUUUGUUACUCUCCAGCUAUUGCCAUGGUUGGCAAGUACUUCAGCAGACGGAAAGCCCUUGCUUAUGGUAUCGCCAUGUCAGGAAGUGGCAUUGGCACCUUCAUCCUGGCUCCUGUGGUUCAGCUCCUUAUUGAACAGUUUUCCUGGCGGGGAGCCUUACUCAUUCUUGGGGGCUUUGUCUUGAAUCUCUGUGUAUGUGGUGCCUUGAUGAGGCCAAUUACUCUUAAAGAGGACCACACAACUCCAGAGCAGAACCAUGUGUGUAGAACUCAGAAAGAAGACAUUAAGCGGGUGUCUCCCUAUUCAUCUUUGACCAAAGAAUGGGCACAGACUUGCCUCUGUUGCUGUUUGCAGCAAGAGUACAGUUUUUUACUCAUGUCAGACUUUGUUGUGUUAGCCGUCUCCGUUCUGUUUAUGGCUUAUGGCUGCAGCCCUCUCUUUGUGUACUUGGUGCCUUAUGCUUUGAGUGUUGGAGUGAGUCAUCAGCAAGCUGCUUUUCUUAUGUCCAUACUUGGAGUGAUUGACAUUAUUGGCAAUAUCACAUUUGGAUGGCUGACCGACAGAAGGUGUCUGAAGAAUUACCAGUAUGUUUGCUACCUCUUUGCCGUGGGAAUGGAUGGGCUCUGCUAUCUCUGCCUCCCAAUGCUUCAAAGUCUCCCUCUGCUCGUGCCUUUCUCUUGUACCUUUGGCUACUUUGAUGGUGCCUAUGUGACUUUGAUCCCAGUAGUGACCACAGAGAUAGUGGGGACCACCUCUUUGUCAUCAGCGCUUGGUGUGGUAUACUUCCUUCACGCAGUGCCAUACUUGGUGAGCCCACCCAUCGCAGGACGGCUGGUAGAUACCACCGGCAGCUACACUGCAGCAUUCCUCCUCUGUGGAUUUUCAAUGAUAUUUAGUUCUGUGUUGCUUGGCUUUGCUAGACUUAUAAAGAGAAUGAGAAAAACCCAGUUGCAGUUCAUUGCCAAAGAAUCUGAUCCUAAGCUGCAGCUAUGGACCAAUGGAUCAGUGGCUUAUUCUGUGGCAAGAGAAUUAGAUCAGAAACAUGGGGAGCCUGUGGCUACAGCAGUGCCUGGCUACAGCCUCACAUGACCAAAGGCCUUGAGCCCCAGAAUCUUCAGGUUUGAGAGAGGUGGGGCCACCAGAUUCUUCAUGUUUCUGAAACUUUUUAUUUUGGCAGAAGGAUUGCCUUCCAAGGAAAUUAUUAUUAUUGUUUUGUUAACAUAUUAAUAUUUAUAAGGGAAAACAGCACAUAAUAAGGAAAGCUGGACUAGCCCAGAGCCUUCUCAUUUGGGAUUUGUGCUCAUAACUGAACUCGUAUCUUUUGGUCAAUGGGCAUAGCUCUGUAAGAAAUGUAAGGACACAGCUGAUAUAAUUAGCUGUAAUUAGGGAUAAUUUCAAAGCAUAACCAAAGCAGAUGACACUGGGCAGCAGCUUUGUUCCAGUCUCAGGCCCUUCAUGUUCCCUCCUCAGAAAGAAAAUGGAAACAUUAACGUGUAGCUUUGCUUACCUUGUUCUGGUUAGAGAAGGGAGGUCAGCUUGGGUGUGGUGGUGAAGAGUGAAGAUGCCAUACUUUUUCAUGGUGGAGUUUCUCAUUAGGGUUUUACUUGGGAUUGUUAAAGAAUACUUGAGAUUCUUCAAAAAGUGGUGAUUAAUAUAGAAAGAAACUCUUAUUUUUUUUUUCUCUUAGUCUUCCAGCCAGCCCUUGCCUCUGCCCAAGGGUAGACACCACUAUGAGAAUCCAAAUAAUCAUGGAAUGCCAUGGUUGGAAUAGAUCUUAAAGGGCAUCUGGUAAGAUCCAUUUGAAAUUGUCCACUGGAAACCGAAAGCUCUUUUCCUAAGACUGGGUUCCAGGCUCUCACAUUUGUUACCAUCACAUAUAAUACUUACUCUAAAUUUAGCAGAACACACUUAGUCACAAGGACAACCUCUCAAUCUUACCUGAAAUGUCAACAACACCAAAACUUCCCGUCUUUUACCUUCAGAGAAGAAGCUCUUACUUAGACUGCAGACGCAUUCCUGUUAGGUUGGAAAAAUGUUGGCAGUAUUCCAAUUGGGCAGGAACUGAAUUCUUGAAUCAGCAGGUCUCUGGUGAGAGUUUUCUUUGCAGAUCAGACAUUUAGUUUUAUCAUUACCCAAAAGAGGAUUGGAGGGAGUCAGUUGUCUGAAAAAUAUUAUCCUAGAGAUAUUCUAAAGGUGAGAUUCCUUUCUCCCUGUGUUAAUUCUUGUUCCACUAUCCACUGCUCUUCAUCUCUUUAUAGAUAAUAAUUAGAAAUCUACUCAUUGGAUUAUAAGUUUAUUCAUUCUCAAAUACUCCACUUUUCUAUGGUUUGGGAUAAUUUCUGAGUCUUCAGAUUGAAGAGGGAAGGCAUGGAGGGAAGAAAAAGUCCAGAUCCCCCAGCUUGUUUCCAACCAUUUUAAGUCCAAAGAAUUAUAAUCCUGAAUCUCACAGUGUGUCACACCUGUAAUAGGAGUAAAUUAUGCAAUCAAUUUUAAUUACCAGGAGUUUAAAAUCCAAAUGUCAAGGAACUGUUUUGACCCUGAAGGCUAUUUAAUCCACUGUCCCCUACAAGGCCUCACAAGUGCUGGGGGAAAAAAAACAGCAAUGAGGAUGAUCCUGAGUUAAUGUGUAUGCUCCGCAAGAGAGCUUGCCUAUACCUUGAUUAUUUCAUAAAAUCACAUGUUAAUACAUUGCUUUCAGAAUGAAAUACUGACUUGAUCUGAUAGGAGAAAAUGGUAAUAUUUCAUAGUUGUUUUCCAAAGACAAAUUUAAAUGUUGUCUGUUAUCUCCUUACUUAGUUUAAGAAUUUAGUUUUGAACCCCAUUGACUUUGUCAUUUGCAAUUUUAAAAAUAUUUGGGACUGGGCAUGGUCGCUCACGCCUGUAAUCCCAGCACUUUGGGAGGCUGAGGCGGGUGGAUCAUGAGGUCAGGAGAUCAAGACCAUCCUGGCUAACAUCGUGAAACUCCGUCUCUACUAAAAAUGCAAAAAAUUAGCCAGGCGUGGUGGCGGGCGCCUGUAGUCCCAGCUACUCAUGAGGCUGAGGCCGGACAAUCGCUUGAACCCAGGAGGUGGAGGUUGCAGUGAGCCAAAAUCAUGCCACUGCACUCCACCCUGGGCGACAGAGCAAGACUCCAUCUCAAAAAAAAAAAAUUGGAAGGUAUCUGUAAAAUGUCAAAGUUAAGAUGAAGUUAUAUCUGUUUGGAAUAGCACUUUGCCCUAAAUAUCAUUUCUUGAAUUUUCAAGCCUAAAGAUGUUUAAAAAUAUGAAUAGUUACAAAUAUUCUUAUACAUAUUUUUUAUCAUGAUCACAACAAAAUUUUGUUUAUGUGGUUCUGCAAUAUAAUUUCUGUGAAGUAUUACAAGUAUUUAUGAAAAAUAAGCAUAGUGAUCAGAAAUUUUAAAGAUUUUGUAUAAAAACAUUUGGGAGAUUUGACUUUAUACAUGCAUAGAUUUGCAUUUUACUUUCCCUUUUGAGGCAGCAUUUUUAGAAAAUCAGUAAGAAAAAUGUACAUCUUAAGGUCUACUAUUUUACAUUUCUACACAGAAUUUUAGUGUUAAUGUUCCAUGUGUCUAUACUGUUUAUUUCAAAACUGAGAAAUUCAUGGGAAUGAUGUAUUUUGUGGAAUCAAGAACAAAAUUAUAGUGGGAUAAUUUUACAUCUUAAAUAUUUCUUUCUACUACUGUAAGCUCUACUUUGGAAUUAUCUGAGUAGAAAAUCAGAAGACAUUAUCUAACUUUGUAGAUACACUGUAUGAUUGGGCUUUUUGUUCAGAUUGUAAUUUCAUUAAUAGAUGAAAUAUUUAUGCUAAUAUUUUCUUAUUUCAAAAGCAAAAUAAAAUGAAUUUAUUGUCCUGUG